AGCGGCCGGGAAGCGCGCCCGAACGAAGCCGCGGCCCGGGCACAGCCAUGGCCCGGCGGGCGGGGGGCGCUCGGAUGUUCGGCAGCCUCCUGCUCUUCGCCCUGCUCGCUGCCGGCGUCGCCCCGCUCAGCUGGGAUCUCCCGGAGCCCCGCAGCCGAGCCAGCAAGAUCCGAGUGCACUCGCGAGGCAACCUCUGGGCCACCGGUCACUUCAUGGGCAAGAAGAGUCUGGAGCCUUCCAGCCCAUCCCCAUUGGGGACAGCUCCCCACACCUCCCUGAGGGACCAGCGACUGCAGCUGAGUCAUGAUCUGCUCGGAAUCCUCCUGCUAAAGAAGGCUCUGGGCGUGAGCCUCAGCCGCCCCGCACCCCAAAUCCAGUACAGGAGGCUGCUGGUACAAAUACUGCAGAAAUGACACCAAUAAUGGGGCAGACACAACAGCGUGGCUUAGAUUGUGCCCACCCAGGGAAGGUGCUGAAUGGGACCCUGUUGAUGGCCCCAUCUGGAUGUAAAUCCUGAGCUCAAAUCUCUGUUACUCCAUUACUGUGAUUUCUGGCUGGGUCACCAGAAAUAUCGCUGAUGCAGACACAGAUUAUGUUCCUGCUGUAUUUCCUGCUUCCCUGUUGAAUUGGUGAAUAAAACCUUGCUCUUUACAUA